AGAGCAGGGGUUGCCUCCCCUCACCCCGGUCCAGGAUGCCCAGUCCCCACGACACCUCCCACUUCCCACUGUGGCCUGGGUGGGCUCAGGGGCUGCCCUUGACCUGGCCUAGAGCCCUCCCCCAGCUGGUGGUGGAGCUGGCACUCUCUGGGAGGGAGGGGGCUGGGAGGGAAUGAGUGGGAAUGGCAAGAGGCCAGGGUUUGGUGGGAUCAGGUUGAGGCAGGUUUGGUUUCCUUAAAAUGCCAAGUUGGGGGCCAGUGGGGCCCACAUAUAAAUCCUCACCCUGGGAGCCUGGCUGCCUUGCUCUCCUUCCUGGGUCUGUCUCUGCCACCUGGUCUGCCACAGAUCCAUGAUGUGCAGUUCUCUGGAGCAGGCGCUGGCUGUGCUGGUCACUACCUUCCACAAGUACUCCUGCCAAGAGGGCGACAAGUUCAAGCUGAGUAAGGGGGAAAUGAAGGAACUUCUGCACAAGGAGCUGCCCAGCUUUGUGGGGCAUUCCAGAGAACCAUGUGCUGUGAGGGCCUUCCGAGUCCAUCUGUUUAAUCCUGUCAUUGGAGACUUGAGAAACCAGAGCCCAGAAGGGAAAAGUGAUUGUCCCAAGAUCACACAGCACUGGAGAAAGUGGAUGAGGAGGGGCUGAAGAAGCUGAUGGGCAGCCUGGAUGAGAACAGUGACCAGCAGGUGGACUUCCAGGAGUAUGCUGUUUUCCUGGCACUCAUCACUGUCAUGUGCAAUGACUUCUUCCAGGGCUGCCCAGACCGACCCUGAAGCAGAACUCUUGACUUCCUGCCAUGGAUCUCUUGGGCCCAGGACUGUUGAUGCCUUUGAGUUUUGUAUUCAAUAAACUUUUUUUGUCUGUUGAUAAUAUUUUAAUUGCUCAGUGAUGUUCCAUAACCCGGCUGGCUCAGCUGGAGUGCUGGGAGAUGAGGGCCUCCUGGAUCCUGCUCCCUUCUGGGCUCUGACUCUCCUGGAAAUCUCUCCAAGGCCAGAGCUAUGCUUUAGGUCUCAAUUUUGGAAUUUCAAACACCAGCAAAAAAUUGGAAAUCGAGAUAGGUUGCUGACUUUUAUUUUGUCAAAUAAAGAUAUUAAAAAAGGCAAA